CUCUCCUGGCUACGACCUCUAAGAGUACUCGGGCCUCGCUGAUGCCUGACGGAGAGCCCUUGGCUUUUGUUGACUUGUUGACCUUUGCUACUGCGAUCUGGUCUUUCUGCGGGGAUAAAGUUCCUCAUUCUGUUGCUUGUCAUUGGGGUUGCCAUCACUCGUUCAGACGGCCGAUUGGCUGACGGUCCCGUCAAUCUCCGGGGACAUGACUAGCCUCAGACACCUCAGAAAAUUGUUCGUUGGUACCCCUACGUGCUGAAAUGAAGAGUUCUGGAGAGAAUCUGAGGGAUUUGAGGAAUUUCAGAUGUUGGGGAUUUUUUCCCCCGCACAGGGAGCGGUAUUCUGCCCUGUCUACACAUUAGAAUCACUUGGCCUGGACAAAAGCUUUUUUAAAAAAGCGUUCCCCUCAUCUCCUCCCCCCAAACCCCGCAUUUCCAUCCACUAGAUUCUAAUGCGUAAGCAGGAGUGACAACUACUGCCCUUGUGCUUUUUUGGGAACAAGAAAUUGUCCAGGGAAAAGAUAAACGCCAAUCAGUCUCUGAUCUCAGUACUAGUCUAUUUUAAGCUAAUUAAGCAUUGAUUUUUUUUUUUAAGUUUAUGACAAACUGCUAUUUUCCAUUCAGUUAAACUAAAUGCGUUUUAAUGAUAGGACGGUAAUUAAUCUAACCUAUUAAUGAAAAGCUGUAUGUCUCGCAGAACUAUGAUAAACUACCUAAUGACGUCAGCUAAGGGUCUAGAAAUGGAAGAAUGAUCGCUAUAUCUUUUUUAAAAAAUAGAAUUUAGGCAUCUUGGGAAAAAAAGAAGCUAAUCUACACUGGAUUUCUGUUAGUGUGAAGACUUUUGUCCCUGUACCUGCUAGGGCUUACCUGUAAAUGAAGUAAGAUGGUCAACACCAGGGAAACAAGUGUUCCUGGUGCCUGGCAGUGGAACACCUUGACUAUCUUGGAAAGAAUUAACUGGCCCCAAGUGGACUUCACAUUUCAUUCCGUGAAGUGGGAGCCUGAGAACAUAUUUUCUGUGUGAGGCUGAAACUGUUGGAGGCUUCCUGAGAUCAUUCUUGAGAAUGGAGCGACCACAUAGGGAAAUAUAGCAUGUUGAUUAAGAGAAUGGACUCUGAAGCCGGAUUUCAUCAGUUUGGAUUUUGGCUUUUCCUCUUUCUAGCAGUUUGGGUUUGAUUUCUGAUGACUCUGGCCUGAGUUCCAGGAUGGUUUUUUCUUGGGACCAGACAUGAACAAAAGUUGACCUCAUGAGCACUUCAACCUCUCCAGCUGCCAUGCUCCUCCGGAGGCUGCGGCGACUCUCCUGGGGCAGCACUGCUGUCCAGCUCUUCAUCCUAACAGUGGUGACGUUUGGCCUGCUGGCCCCCCUGGCCUGUCACCGACUUCUACACUCUUACUUCUAUCUGCGCCAUUGGCAUCUGAACCAAAUGAGCCAAGAGUUCCUGCAGCAAAGCUUGAAAGAGGGUGAGGCUGCCCUCCACUAUUUUGAGGAGCUUCCCUCUGCCAAUGGCUCAGUGCCCAUUGUCUGGCAGGCCACCCCCCGGCCCUGGCUGGUGAUCACCAUCAUCACUGUGGACAGGCAGCCUGGCUUCCACUACGUCCUGCAGGUUGUGUCCCAGUUCCACCGGCUUCUUCAGCAAUGUGGCCCCCAGUGCGAGGGGCACCAACUCUUCCUGUGCAACGUGGAGCGUAGUGUGAGCCAUUUUGAUGCCAAGUUGCUCUCCAAGUAUGUCCCUGUGGCCAAUCGCUAUGAGGGCACUGAGGAUGAUUAUGGUGAUGACCCUUCGACCAACUCGUUUGAGAAAGAGAAGCAGGACUAUGUCUAUUGCCUGGAGUCAUCCCUGCAGACCUACAACCCAGACUACGUCCUGAUGGUAGAAGACGAUGCUGUACCAGAAGAGCAGAUCUUCCCAGUCUUGGAGCACCUUCUGCGGGCUCGCUUCUCUGAGCCACAUCUCAGAGAUGCCCUUUAUCUCAAGCUGUAUCACCCCGAGAGGCUCCAGCACUACAUCAAUCCAGAGCCCAUGCGGAUCCUGGAAUGGGUUGGUGUAGGCAUGUUGCUGGGGCCCUUACUAACCUGGAUAUACAUGAGGUUUGCCAGCCGCCCAGGGUUUAGCUGGCCUGUAAUGCUCUUCUUCUCCCUGUAUAGCAUGGGUCUGGUGGAGCUGGUGGGUCGGCACUAUUUCCUGGAACUGCGGCGGCUGAGUCCUUCCCUGUACAGUGUGGUUCCUGCCUCUCAGUGUUGCACCCCAGCCAUGCUCUUCCCGGCACCUGCGGCCCGCCGGACCCUCACCUACCUGUCCCAAGUGUACUGCCACAAGGGCUUUGGCAAGGACAUGGCACUGUACUCGCUGUUGAGGGCCAAGGGAGAGAGGGCCUAUGUAGUGGAGCCGAACCUCGUGAAACACAUCGGGCUCUUCUCCAGUCUCCGGUACAACUUUCAUCCCAGUCUCCUCUAGGGUGCCAAGAGAUGCCUUUCUGAAGUUGGCCACUUCUUGAAGAUUCAAAUAUUUAUCUCUUUAUUUAGACAUGGUUGCCUGCAGGUAUUUCACUGUUUACUGUUGUUAGAGAUAUAGGCACUGGGGCAGCUGAGGAACCUCAAUAUGUUAAGAGCCUUGGCUUUGGUAGCCUCCUGGCAGGAGCAGCAGUUUGCCACAGGUCCGGACCUCUCCCUCCACACAGCCACACUGCCUCAUGCAGUCUGACCCACCCAGUGAGGGUGCAUUUGAACACUGAUUAUAUUCUCCAUUUGUUUUUAAGCUCUGCUUUGUGUUAGAGCUUGUGACUGCCAAAAAUUUUGUGCACAGUGAUAUGACUGUUUUAGGAUCUUAAGGGUAGAAUUUUGUGAAAGGUGAGAUCCUUUGGAAUUGAGUUCUUUCUCAUUGGGUAUGAAAAUGGAUGUAUGUUUAGAAUAUAUGCCCAACGAGGCAGGACCAUGUGGAUAGAUUCCAUUUGUUUCCUUGACCUGAUGUAAUAAAAACUGAUAAAAGCCGUGCAGUGCCCGGCAUCUUGGAGGCAGGUGAUCUGGCUUUUCUGUUACCUGGGAUUUUCUUUUCCUAUAUAUCUGUAGUGCACUGAUAAUUGAUAUUGUUAGUGAGAACUUUAAGGCACGACAAGAUCUGGAAGAGCUUGUGAACCAUCAAAGUCAGAUUGCUUAUGUUGAGUAGUGAUUUAACAUUGAACAUUUCUGUACUACUCUGACUCUUUGAAAAUUGGACAUUUCAGAAUGAUACAAUAUAGGGGAGCUCUUUACAAGUAGCAUAUCAUUUUUCCUGACUUUCCUGGCUGACUGCUUACCUUCAUUUCUUUUUCUUCUAGGUAGCAUGAUGUUAUAGAAAAAAAAAAAAAAAAAUCAUGGACUGAAGUCAGAAGACCUGACCUUUUAUUUCAGAUCUCUGCCAUGGCCUAACGACGUGACCACCUUGGGCAGGUCAUAUAAUCACUCUGGGUCUCAAUUUCUUCACCUGUAAAAUGAGGACAGUAAUACUUACAUGUUAAAGUUGCCUUGAGGAUUAAAUGGCAGAAUAUAUGUAAAACACCUAGCAAGUGCUUAGUCCAUAGAAGACGCUUGGCAAACUUUUCUCUCCUAUAAUAAACAUAUACAACUCAAGCUUAUUUCGGAAAAAGAUAUUGGUGAUGUUGUUUAAAGUAUGAGAUAGGGCAUGGAGCUGCCACCUAUGUACCAGCUAUUCCAGAUGACCAAGCCCUGCUAGAAUAAAGACUGACUUUUCAUUGUGACCUCUGAAGGAUGUGCAGCUCAGCUUUCACCUAUCCCCACGUUCACCCAAGCCAAAAAGAAGAAUUGUUCAUUCAAACUGGAAAUGAUCUCCAGCUUGGAAAUGAGACUCCUCAUGAGCUUAUUCUAAGAUCAGAGUCUGAAAAUUAUUUUCUCAAAAGUUACAAAUAAAUGUCUUUUAACAGUACUGUCAGACUAGUGACCAACAAGUUACUUUAUGAGGAUGGAUGAUGAUAUUAGAGUUCAAGCAAUUGUCCAGUUUGUUUCGAUGCCACAGUUUGCUUUUAAAUUCCCAUAGUGAGCUUCCAUCUUGAGACCCACUCAACACAGAAGGAUUACAUAAAGGUUGAUCACCCACGCUCUACAGAUGAACAAAUUGAGACCCAGAGAUGCUAAACUGCUCUGCAGGUCACAAACCUGAACAGCAGCAUAGCCAAAAUGGGAACGGAGCUCUUCUGACUUCAAGCCCCUGCACUUUUUUCUUAACCACAUUAAUUUUAUGAAUAUCUAUGUGGUCAAAGUCUCUUUUGUAAAAUCUGAGUAUAAGCUGAACUAGAUCAUGUCUCUGUAAGCUAAGAUGGCAGAAACACAUUGUCAUGUUAGUUUGGAGGAGCAAACAGAUAUAAGUAUGUGUUGUAAUGUUAUAGUGAGCUGUUAUGUAUCCCCCAGCAAUGUCCAAAGUGAUCAGAGCUACUAGAUGACUUAUUACAAUGUUCAGAUCCCACUCCUUCAUUCCUCCUCUCUCAGUGACCUGUCUACCCCCAAGCUUUAGAACUGAGCUCUCUCCAACUUAGAACUCAUUAGAGUUUGUUGCAUUAGUGAUUGGAUCUCCUCAUGAAAGUUUUUUGACCAAUGACAGUAGAGCCCCUUUAAGCUAGCCAGGCCCAAGAUAGGGAAGCACUGCUGGUUUACAUUUCUGCUCUUUCUAAUUCAGUUGUCUAUUGCAUGCAGACAUCCCCUGCCCGACUUCUCCAUUAUGGAAGGCUAAGGCCAUCCUUCCUUGUCCAGUUUCUCUACCUACACACUAACAUGCCUUUUCCCCAUGGAGUGAACUCUGCCAGUUGUCUUUGGACAUUUUCUGCAGAUGCAGGCUCAGUUCUGCUCUUUUGUUCCCACCCACUUCUAGAUCUUCCUCCAUUUAAUCCCUUAUUCUUAUAAGGAGUCUAAUUUUUGUGUAUUGUCCUUGAUUAGGGCAGCUGACAGCUUUACACCAAAGCUGAAGUCUCUCACUUAAUCCUAAGCAAGGGGCUAGGGAGAACUAAGAUAUCCUUCCCAUAUCAAGGGAUAUAGGUUACUAGAAGGGUGGAGGUCUCUUAACAGGCUCACUCACCUUUCAGAGUUUAAAUUAUGGUCAGGCUUAAGAAGCUCUCUCUUGUGACUGAGUGUAUUGCAUAGACAUGUCUGUGAAAAUAAAAGCACCCAUUUUGCUAAGGC